AGUGGGACACUGCAGGGUGCGGGGACAACUACGAAGAUGGCGGUUGCGCGCUUGGCAGCUGUGGCGGCCUGGGUACCUUGUCGGAGCUGGGGCUGGGCAGCCGUCCCCUUCGGUCCCCACCGUGGCCUCAGCGUGCUGCUUGCACGGAUACCUCAGCGGGCGCCACGGUGGCUCCCAGCUUGUAGACAAAAGACGUCACUCUCAUUCCUUAAUCGACCAGACCUUCCAAACCUGGCUUAUAAGAAGCUAAAAGGCAAAAGUCCAGGAAUUAUCUUCAUCCCUGGCUAUCUUUCUUAUAUGAAUGGUACAAAAGCGUUGGCGAUUGAGGAGUUUUGCAAAUCUCUAGGUCACGCCUGCAUAAGGUUUGAUUACUCAGGAGUUGGAAGUUCAGAUGGUAACUCAGAGGAAAGCACACUGGGGAAAUGGAGAAAAGAUGUUCUUUCUAUAAUUGAUGACUUAGCUGAUGGGCCACAGAUUCUUGUUGGAUCUAGCCUUGGAGGGUGGCUUAUGCUUCAUGCUGCAAUUGCACGACCAGAGAAGGUCGUGGCUCUUAUUGGUGUAGCUACAGCUGCAGAUACCUUAGUGACAAAGUUUAAUCAGCUUCCUGUUGAGGACUCUGGAAGGAAAAACUAUAUUUCUUUACAUUCAGCCUAAAAUUGCAUGACUAAAAAAGGAAGUAGAGAUGAAAGGUGUGUGGAGCAUGCCAUCAAAAUACUCUGAAGAAGGAGUUUAUAACGUUCAGUACAGUUUCAUUAAAGAAGCUGAACAUCACUGCUUGUUACAUAGCCCAAUUCCUGUGAACUGCCCCAUAAGAUUGCUCCAUGGCAUGAAGGAUGACAUUGUACCUUGGCAUACAUCAAUGCAGGUUGCCGAUCGAGUACUCAGCACAGAUGUGGAUGUCAUCCUCCGAAAACACAGUGAUCACCGAAUGAGGGAAAAAGCAGACAUUCAACUUCUUGUUUACACUAUUGAUGACUUAAUUGAUAAGCUCUCAACUAUAGUUAACUAGUAUCACAUGUUUAGUUGGUAUGUAAACUAAUGUAUCCAGAAGAUUGGAAGAGGGAUAAGAAAUGAAAGAUCCUGAUACUUUAGGUUUUUCCCUUUCCUCUAUUUUGUAAAUAUAAGAUGAGUAUUAUUUAAUGAUGUAUUUGCAUAAGUAAUGCAAAUUGUGAAGAAGGACCAGCUGCUGUUUAGAAAAUUUUCUCCUUCCUUCUGUCCUUGAUUUUUUUUCAUUAAAGUAUUUCCUUUUUUUAAUUCAAGAAAAGUUUACCUUUCUUAUGCUUAUGUUAGCUAUGCCAGCUCUUAAUUGCAUCCUUUUCUAAUUAGGAUUAUUAAUAAAGCGUGAAUAUUUUGUUUUUUAUUAUAGACAGAAAUUUGUAACAUUACUUCUGAUUUGAAAAUGCAAUUCACAAAAUAUAGGGAAAUUUUUAUUGAAGUAAAUUUGAAAUGAUGGAGAAAUUUCAGAAGCAUAAUAAAGUUCACAAUAAGGAUAAUACUUUAUAUAAUGUAUAAAGUAUAUAUAAUAUAAUAUAUAUGUUAUAUAAACUGCACAUUAUAUUCAAACUUAAAAUUGAGCUUUUUUUUUAAAGGCCCAAAAUUGUACAGUGAUACAAGGAGCUAUUUCUAAAAUUUGGCUUAUGUAUAAUAUAUUUAAAUGGGGAAUUUCAUCUAAAACAAUGAUGUAGUAUUUUUAAUAUUCUGAUUGGUAAAAUUAAAGAGGAAAUUAAUCUUUAUAUAUUAUUUCUUGCAGAAACAUUCAUUAUUUUAUUAAUAUUGCCCUAAGUACAACUAGGCAAGUGAUUGCCACCUAAAUCAGAAGACGUUCUAAAGUCAGUAAGAAAGUGUGAAAUGCUAGUAUAAAGGUUAUUUUUUUUCUUUCCUAAAUAACUAAAGUGAGGUGUAGAUUGAGCCUUGAUAUUAUUUAGUUAAUGUUUUUUAUUAAUUAAUUUUGGCUGGACUUUAUUUAGCUUGAUUAGGUUAUUAUCUGUCAAACCUUUUAAGUUGACAACAUGACUCAUAUAUAUACAUGUGUAUAAGAUGAGCAUGUGUCGAAGACUUAUUCGACUCAUUAAUGAGGAAACCAGCAGAUAGUAAACCUGGUUCAAAGUACAAUUCAAGAAACUGAGUAUUUAUGGGCAUUGAAGAAAAAAUGUUGAGAUAAAAUUGCUGUGCAGAAAAAAGUGUUAAUGAAGCCGACCUGACUACUUAACCUUAGAGACCUGCUUUACAAGGUUGGCCCUUGAUUGGCAUCUGGGAACUUGGAGUUCAGGGGGCUUCCACCAUUCCCAGAACUGAUCAAAGUAGCUUACUAUAUCUAAACUGUAAAACAAUAUAGUUUCUCCUGAACACCUGCUUUCCUUCUGGGAGUCUGGAAUUUUGGUAUGUGCCAGGCAGAGACUACCUUUGUGACCAGCUCCCAGUAAAAACCCCAGGCACUCAGUCUCUAACAAGCUUUUCUGGUUGACAGUGUUUCACAAGUGCUGUUACAACUGGUUGCUGGGAGAAUUAAGCUCAUCCUCUGUGAUUCCACUGGCGGAGGAUUCUUGGAAGCUUGCACUUAGUUUCCCCUGACUUCACCCCAUGUGUCUUUUUUCCUUUGCUGAUUUUGUUUUGUAUCCUUUCACUGUAAUAAAUCAUGGCCGUGAGCAGAACUGUA